GCUCAAUACCCCAAGCAAUACCUGCAACUGAGGAUUCUUCCCGGGGAGACCGCAGCCCAUCGGCAUGGCUCAAGAGUUUGUGAACUGCAAAAUCCAGCCUGGGAAGGUGGUUGUGUUCAUCAAGCCCACCUGCCCGUACUGCAGGAGGGCCCAAGAGAUCCUCAGUCAAUUGCCCAUCAAACAAGGGCUUCUGGAAUUUGUCGAUAUCACAGCCACCAACCACACUAACGAGAUUCAAGAUUAUUUGCAACAGCUCACGGGAGCAAGAACGGUGCCUCGAGUCUUUAUUGGUAAAGAUUGUAUAGGCGGAUGCAGUGAUCUAGUCUCUUUGCAACAGAGUGGGGAACUGCUGACGCGGCUAAAGCAGAUUGGAGCUCUGCAGUAACCACAGAACAGGCCCCAUGCUGACGUCCCUCCUCAAGAGCUGGAUGGCAUUGCAAAUGAUGACAGCACUUCUGGUGGAUGAAUUUGGGGGCACAAACAGCUUUUUUCCUCUUUUGGCUCAGUAUUUAAAAGUGGACCAACUUGCUCUUAAUCACAGGGCCAAGAAGGUUGACGGGCCAUCUUGGUUUUCUUCUGGAUGUGCUCUUUGGUUUUCAGAAGACUGUGACAAGUUCUGGCCCAGGAUUCGCUCACUGACCCUCAAUUGUCCUCUUUGGCAUGCGUUUCUUACUGUUCUCCAUGUGUCGGCAUGUCUCUACCUCUAAGCCAGUGUUUUUCAACUAUGUUUAUCCAGACUCCUUCUCCACAAUGAUGAAUCCACAGUUGGUUAUCUGCUACUGCCCAUUAGCUAAAAUCAUUUUGCUGCUUGACUUUAUGGAGUUUGUAUUAUGAAAUCAGUGGGUAUUUUGAAUGUGUUCUUUCUAACUACAUGCAUCUCUCCACUCAACUCCACCCCAUCCCAUCCCACCUUGAAAAUCACUGCUCUGAACCAGUGUUCUCCACCUUGUCCUCCACAGAUCUCAUAGGAAAUGUUCAACAAUUCUGUGAAAGGUCACAGGACCCAAUUGGAGAAAUCAUAUGAAAAGCAUAGUUGGUCUUGGUGUCAUAUGGAUCAGAGGCACAAGUGCAGAGGCUGUGGUCAUGCGGAACACUCUGUUAUUUAAGAUGGCUAUCCAGAUAAUCCUGAACACUGUGUAUUUAUUUUAUUUAGACUACCAGCAAAGAUUAAAGCAUGAAAUGUAAAACAUCUGAUAAAACUUACAGCCCCCUACACCAAGAGUGUAUCUGUGAAAGAGCUCCUACACUUUGAAAACUUAAGAAUCCCUUAUCAUGAAGUUUGCCUGUUCUAGAAUUGUAAGAUUGUUAAUUUCCUUCAAUCUCUAGUGACAACACUUAAUUUCUUUUCUAAUAAAAAAAACCUAUAGAUGAUUCAGUGAUUUUUGUCCAAUUCAUUUGCAUGUUCUCAAGACAUUAAGGAAUGUUAUGCGAAAUACACUAACUUAAAACUGUGUUUAUAUUUGGCCCUGCCAUUAUAAAUAAAGACACGUGCUGCUGUCA